AGAGCCAAGCGGCGGGCUGGCGGCGGGCUCCGACGUCUGCGCCAGGACCUGGCUGGCUGAGCCCGGCGCAGCAGCAGCAGCCAGGGCAGCGCGGCCCCUACUCCCUGUCAGGUCGUAGAGGCGAGCAGGGACCAGCUGGUCGCCGGCCCCUCGGGCAAGAUGGGGAACCGGGAGAUGGAGGAGCUGAUCCCGCUGGUGAACCGUCUGCAGGACGCGUUUUCGGCGCUGGGACAGAGCUGCCUGCUGGAGCUGCCGCAGAUCGCCGUGGUGGGCGGCCAGAGCGCCGGCAAGAGCUCGGUGCUCGAGAACUUCGUGGGCAGGGACUUUCUCCCUCGAGGGUCGGGCAUUGUAACAAGACGACCUCUUGUGCUGCAGCUUGUUACUUCUAAAGCAGAAUAUGCCGAGUUUCUACAUUGCAAAGGAAAGAAAUUUACAGAUUUUGAUGAAGUUCGCCUUGAGAUUGAAGCAGAAACAGAUCGCGUGACUGGAAUGAAUAAAGGCAUUUCCUCCAUACCCAUUAAUUUACGAGUCUAUUCCCCACACGUGUUAAAUCUAACCCUUAUUGAUCUACCUGGAAUAACUAAAGUGCCUGUGGGAGAUCAGCCACCAGAUAUCGAGUAUCAGAUCAGAGAAAUGAUUAUGCAGUUCAUCACGAGGGAGAACUGUCUGAUUUUAGCUGUUACUCCAGCCAACACUGAUCUUGCAAACUCAGAUGCGCUGAAGCUAGCUAAAGAAGUUGAUCCUCAAGGUCUGAGAACCAUUGGAGUUAUCACCAAACUGGACCUUAUGGAUGAAGGAACGGAUGCCAGGGAUGUUCUAGAGAACAAACUGUUGCCUCUUCGCAGGGGUUACGUGGGGGUGGUAAACAGAAGCCAGAAGGACAUAGAUGGGAAGAAGGACAUAAAGGCAGCCAUGCUGGCAGAGAGGAAGUUUUUCCUUUCCCACCCGGCUUACAGACAUAUCGCUGACCGAAUGGGAACCCCACACCUGCAGAAGGUCCUUAAUCAGCAACUUACCAACCACAUUCGGGAUACCCUACCAAACUUCAGGAACAAACUACAGGGACAGUUGCUCUCCAUAGAACAUGAAGUAGAAGCCUACAAAAAUUUCAAACCAGAAGACCCAACAAGGAAGACCAAAGCAUUGCUGCAGAUGGUUCAGCAAUUUGCUGUGGACUUUGAGAAGAGAAUUGAAGGGUCAGGGGAUCAAGUAGAUACCCUGGAACUCUCAGGUGGUGCUAAAAUCAAUCGUAUUUUUCAUGAACGCUUUCCUUUUGAGAUAGUAAAGAUGGAGUUCAAUGAGAAAGAAUUGCGAAGAGAAAUAAGCUAUGCAAUCAAAAACAUACAUGGUAUCAGGACAGGGUUGUUUACUCCAGACAUGGCAUUUGAAGCGAUAGUCAAGAAACAGAUUGUAAAGUUGAAAGGGCCUUCCUUGAAGAGUGUGGAUCUGGUAAUACAAGAAUUAAUCAACACUGUGAAGAAGUGUACCAAAAAACUGGCAAACUUCCCCAGACUCUGCGAGGAAACGGAAAGGAUUGUUGCUAACCACAUUCGUGAGCGAGAAGGGAAGACAAAGGACCAGGUAUUGCUAUUGAUUGACAUUCAAGUCUCUUACAUCAACACCAACCAUGAAGACUUCAUUGGCUUCGCAAAUGCUCAGCAGAGGAGCAGUCAGGUUCACAAGAAAACCACAGUUGGAAAUCAGGGAACCAAUCUUCCGCCUUCAAGGCAAAUUGUGAUUCGCAAGGGGUGGCUCACCAUCAGCAACAUUGGCAUCAUGAAAGGCGGCUCGAAGGGAUACUGGUUCGUCCUUACUGCGGAAAGCUUGUCCUGGUAUAAAGAUGAUGAGGAAAAAGAAAAGAAGUACAUGCUUCCCUUGGACAACCUGAAAGUUCGGGAUGUGGAAAAGAGCUUUAUGUCUAGCAAGCACAUCUUUGCACUCUUUAAUACAGAGCAAAGGAAUGUAUACAAAGACUAUCGCUUCCUUGAGCUGGCAUGUGAUUCCCAGGAGGAUGUCGACAGCUGGAAGGCAUCUCUACUAAGAGCUGGGGUCUAUCCUGACAAAUCUGUAGCUGAAAAUGAUGAGAAUGGACAAGCAGAAAACUUUUCCAUGGACCCACAAUUGGAGAGGCAAGUGGAGACCAUUCGCAACCUCGUAGACUCCUACAUGUCCAUUAUCAACAAAUGUAUCCGAGAUCUAAUUCCAAAAACAAUAAUGCACCUUAUGAUCAAUAACGUUAAAGAUUUCAUAAAUUCCGAGCUCCUAGCACAGUUGUAUUCUUCAGAGGACCAAAAUACCCUGAUGGAGGAAUCUGCUGAGCAGGCUCAGCGCCGGGAUGAGAUGCUUCGAAUGUAUCAAGCACUGAAAGAAGCCCUUGGGAUAAUUGGGGACAUCAGCACAGCCACCGUGUCCACUCCGGCACCCCCUCCAGUGGAUGACUCCUGGAUACAGCACUCUCGCAGGUCACCUCCUCCAAGCCCCACAACCCAAAGGAGGCCAACACUAAGUGCUCCCCUCGCAAGGCCCACAUCCGGCCGAGGACCAGCUCCUGCCAUUCCCUCUCCUGGCCCCCACUCUGGGGCUCCUCCAGUCCCAUUCCGUCCAGGCCCAUUACCUCCUUUCCCCAGCAGCAGUGACUCCUUCGGAGCCCCUCCACAAGUUCCAUCUAGGCCUACGAGGGCCCCGCCCAGUGUCCCAAGGUUUGGUGCCAUGAAGGAUGAAGCUGCUGAGCCCUGAAGUCGUGGGCUAAGGGUACACGGACAAUUAAGCAACUUAAGUGACUAGCCUGUGUCUGAUUCCCCUGCAGUCAUGUACUGAAAACCUCCUGACUUACUGUCUUUUCAACAGCCCUCUAAAAGUCUGACUUCUUUUAGCAGCUGAAUGUCAUUUGGACAAAUGAGGAACUCAUCUUGUGACCUCUGAUGUCAGCCAGGAGCUUUCUAUUUUUCUCACCAUCCUCCCCCUUUAAAAAACAAAUACAUAAAUUUAUCAUUGGGCAUUGUGAUUUUUCAUGGAACAGUUUUUAUUUUUAGCAACUGGCUUUCAAAGCAAGGAAAGAUGUUUUUUUAAGCAUAAUUACUAAGAAUAGAAACAACUUUGAGGUGUUCUUUUUGAUUCUUAAUAUUUAAGGUGUCUCAUGACAUUUGAAGUCUCUAAAUGUCAUUAAUCAUUUGUUGCAGGUUUAAUAUGAGUUGUCAUGAUGCUUAAUAUACUUUAAUGAAAAUAGAAUUUUGGCCACAUGCUGUUCAUUAAAGAAAAUAUCCAAUUUAAUAUAAGUCCCUCAAUUAAAAAUCCCAUCAAAAGCCUUGUUCCAAUUUCACCAUGAUUCUGGCUAUAACACAAUUAUUUCAUUGGAGUGAAUCAAUGGUUAAUGUCAAAGUUUUUAAUUCUUCAAGUCUUGGUUUCAAUCUGGUUUAAGUGAAAGUAAAAUUAGUUUGGUGGUUUCCUUCUUGAGUCUUGCAAACUUGAGUCUACCUUACACAAACAUCUCCAUCCUGCCACGGUUCGGAUGACUGGCAGUCUGUUUAGGCGAGGCCCAGAAACAGAAAGCAAGUCUUGUGAAAGUCAGAAUCUGGGAGCUUUGCAGAUGCGUCAAGGUAGCCUUCAGAUUGCCUCUCUGUUUUCAAUGUGUCCCCUAUCUCACUCUUCCAAACAUCCUAUGCUGUAAGAGGGUAAAAGGAAAAGGAAAAUAAGAAAGGAUCUACAUAAGGCAAAGUACAAGUAACAUAAAUGCAGACAGCAGCAGUAAAUAUAACAAUAUGCUGCUGUUAGCCCAGUGGUAACUGGCAUUAAGCUAACCAAACACAACUGCUUCCACAUCCCAUGACAAAUAAUAGCAAAUAGCUCUGUCAUUGUUCUCUUUGGGGCUCUAAAUUGUUGAAGCUUCAGCCAUUGCAGGGAAAGCCUUCCUGAGUUUCAGGGGACCAAGCCCUGCCCUGAGUUUCACCUGACUGAUAGAGGAAAACAGCCAAGACAGGAGUCUGGCAGAGAAGCCACUGGCCAGUGAAAAAUGCACAGUAGAGGAUUAUUAUUCUUCCUGCAACCAGUCAGUAGCAAAUUGUCACCAGUUGGAAUCUGCUGAAUAUUCCUAUAUACAAGUUAAUGUUAGCUCAAAGAAAGGGGGGUUUAAAAAAAAAAGUUUUGCCCAGUGUAAGCAGAUACAGAUUUGUAGAUGACACACAAGCUAGUACUUCUAUUUCAUCACUGCACUUCGUUGUUUCCCUCACUUGUAAGAAAAGAAUGAUUUUUACAGGGAAACCUUCACAUUCAGACAGUUCUUGUUAUUUCUUGUUUUAACGACGUCAACGAUUCAUGGCAUGACAUUGCUCAUAGCUCUUUCACCUCUAAAUUUUAUCCAAGCAACAAAUUAGAAGAAAGGACUGCUGGGGAACUUCUUCCUUCUUUCUGUGAAAGAUCAGAAGCAAUUUUUUUUUUUUUUUUUUUGAGGCGGAGUCUCUAUCACCCAGGCUGGAGUGCAGUGGCGUGGUCUCGGCUCACUGCAACCCCUGCCUCCUGGCUUCAAGCGAUUCUCCUGCCUCAGCCUCCUGAGUAGCUGGGAUUACAGGCGUGCACCACCACAUCCAGCUAAUUUUUGUAUUUUGAGUAGAGAUAGGGUUUCACCAUGUUGCCCAGGUUGGUCUCAAACUCCUGACCUCAGGUGAUCCACCCACCACAGCCUCCCAGAGUGCUGGGAUUACAGCCAUGAGCCACCACACCAGGCCUAGAAGCAAAAUUUAAAUAACGUUUACUAGAGUUGCUUUAGCCAAUAAGAGCCAGGAAAUUAAAAAUGAAAAUGUAAAUGCUUCAUCUUUCACUCAGAAACAUGCCUUAAAUGCCUACCUCCAGCAAUGUAAGAAAAACAUUGAGGAUUUAGCUGAGAGUUUGAUGGCUUUUGCUUGCCUGUCAUAACUUCAUUGCUGCUCAAAGGGAGAAUUUUAAAACACUCGACAUUGAAAUCCUUUAGCUUACCAUUGCCAAUGUAUUGUAAGUGUUGUCGGGGGGAACCCCUGAAUCUAAACAUAUAUUUACACCCUUAAGUUGCCAAAUUAAAUCCAUCUGGCUUACCAAAUGCUGUCGCCAAAAGACUGUUACACUGUUGGUGUGGCCAGUAUUUUAAAUGUGGGGGAUGGGAGGGCAGUGUUGAAAGGCACUAGAUUUGAUGAUAGAAUUUACAUGUGCAUUGAUGCCACAUUAAGUAUUUACAUCAAGUUUAGAUCCCAUGGCAACUCUGACCAAGAAAGAAUUCCUACACAAGGCAAGAAGUCUAAAGCCGCUAGGUAUUUGCGCCGUCUCCUCAUGGCACUUUUUGCCCUGUGACUGCUUUUCAGGCAUCACAGCCACGCAAUAGGCAAAACCACAAAUAGCAAACACUCUAAUUUCUUGAAUUAUUUUUUAACUAUUCCCAUAAGCACUAGGAAAUGCCCACUCCUGUUUUCUGGUCGAAGUUAUCAGCUCAUGUGAAUCAUAGAAAGAAUAAAUUCUACCCAAGGACCUGAAAAUAUGUUAAGUCAAAAUGGCAAGUAGCAAAAUUCGCAGUCACUCAUAAUCCAUAGCAAGGUAGGGUCUUCCUAACUUCAGUUGCUUAGAGACAUGUAAAAUUCCAAAUGUUCAUAAAAUCAACUUUUUCUCCUAUUGGGAAUUAAUUUAAACAUUAGAAAACAGGAAAAGGUAUAAGCACUCUUCUUAAAUGUGCAAGUUGAUAUGAAAUUUAGAAAUAAGCCCCAUUCCUUCCCUGCUUCUUUGGUAGAAGGGCUAAUGGACUAACUAAGAGAGAGAAUAAGCUAAAAGUCUGGAUAGCCACAACUAAAUACACCACCACAGGAGAAUCCCUCAGCUUCUAUGGUAAUUUUGAAACUAAGAGAAAAUAAGACAGCAUGAGAAGGCAUUAUGCUGCUUUAAAUAUGACUUGGGAAUGGUCUUAUUUUACAAUCAAAUAUACCACUUGCUUCCAUCAUGUAAAUAUUACCAGUAUUUAGUUUCAGAUUUUCAUGAGGUAACAUUAUCUAAAUUUACUGUUCGUCUGUAUAUUUAAAUAUAUAACAUUCAUUUGCAGUAUUUCAUUUAUCUCAAAAGAUUAGUAUAUAUCUCAUCUAGAAUGAGACCUCUUAUGAGAAUAGGAGAUGAGAAAGACUUUUAAAGGCAUUUCGCAGUCCAGAGAGUCUGCAAUGAAAUUAUUCCACUCAGGAAUGGGUAUUUAUGUAAGAUACAUUCUGUACCAUGUGUAUUUUUUUAAGUUUAUAUUAGCAUUAUUCUCAAAGCCAAUUUUAAGAGUGAAUGAAAUUGUUCCCUUAAGUAAAUCUACCCUUAAGUAGUAUCAUGCUCAAGGGCCUACACCAGAAAGUCUGCCCCACUGCUCUCGCUAUAAUACCAUUCACUGAGGAAAAGCUGUAAGAACUGAGGAAAAUGUCUACUUACUUCUUAAAACAACGAGAAUUGCUUUUUGCUUCUCAGUAGUGUUGGAAACUAUUUUAAUAACUAAAAUAAUAAAACUUCAUGUGAGGCAAAUUCCACCUUAAUUAUUGCCCUUUGGGGUGGAAAAAUUAAGGAAACAUUAGUAAAUGUGUUAAACAGAAAAACCACUGCAGUAAUUUCCCGCCAAAUACCUGGGUCUAAAGUCAAAAUAAAAUCUGUGCUCUGCGUAUGAUUUGUAUGAAAGCAGACUUAUAGUUUUAGCUCUAACAAUAGUACCACUUAGGACUAAGAUGAAUGGACCAGAAAAACCCCUGUGACUCAUCAGUAGACUGUGAUUAGCUUACUUAAGUGUUCUACAGUUCAGUUCGGGAAUCUUUAAUGAAGGAUAUUGAUAUAAUUGCUUGAUUCAUUUUAAUAUUUCAAACACUCUAAAUUACUCCAUCACUAUCUUAAUAAUUAAUGCAUGAAAACUCAUACUUACAUUGAAAAUUCAUUUUAAAGCACAAUAUCUUUGAAUAAACCCAUUGAAAUAGUGUUUCUGGUGUUUGCUUAAAACUUUGGUGUAUAACUGAUUACAUCUUAUAGAUUUCAUUUUUUUUUUCCUGGUAUUUUCCUCUUCUAACUUAGGACCUUUUUGCCAUAUGUGGCUAUUUGAUGUAUAUUGUUCAGUCACGAUCUUCUAGGUGACUGAAAAACGCAUGGAGUUACUCAUGCCAAUAAUUAUUGCUACUGAAUUGUUCCAAAGUCUCCCUUCCUGCAGAAAAAUAAGUUUCAGUAAAAUAUUCUAGAGGAUUACAAGUUAUCUUUGCAGUUCAUAAAUACUUUCAUAGGCUCCAUUGAUAUUCACAGUUUUCAGUUAGAAUGUUAUUUUUAUUGCAAAGUUUGCAUUUAUAUUUCUUUUCUGUGGAUUGCUUACCACUUAUUAAAAUUAAAAUGCAUUUUAAGGUGAAACAUUAUGUACCUAGAAUACUGAAGGUAGCACUGACCAUUGUCUUUAGCUCAGAAAGCAAUGUUGAAUUGGAAAAGCAAGAUUUGAGAAUAUUCCUCUUUACUGCAUUGUCAUUGCACUCUAGUCCUUCUGAUUUCCCUUGUUUCUCAGAUGAUCCCUACGCCCAAUUAUACAGAACAGUCUUCCUCUAGUUACUUAUAUCAAACACUUGCCUGCUAGCUGUGUUUGGCAGGCCAGCAGGAUGAGGUAAUAAUCAGAAGAAAAUGUUCUGGUUUAUUGGCCUCAUCCACGUACAACAUUAUUCAAAAUAGUUCUCUGUGGGUGAGAACAGAGUUGCUUUGAGAUCCCCUGGUCUAAUGUUCUGUAGUAGUGAGGAGGAACAAAACUGUAAACUUUUUUGAUCUCUUCUAGAAUAAUGGUAAGGUAAAUGAUAUCUGCUUGGCCCAUCCUUUCAGUAAUGUUUACAGGCAGUUAGAUGUAUGUGAAAAUGAGAGCCUUUCAUUUAUAAACAUUUUGGCUUUACUCUUUCCAAGUCCAGCCAUCUUCUUACGUACAGCCUCCAUGGUCAGUACAGCAGUGUUUUCCUAAAAGCAUAUUUUGUGAACAAUUUCUCCAGGAUGAUGGUAGUUUUUGUAAGACAGAUGCCUAAAAGACAUAUGGUUUUCAUAGAUUUUCCGUCUAGACUAGCUUUAUUUAGUGACUUUUGGUCUGAAUUGGUCUAGUUAAAGUUUCUGUAGGAGCUUGUAUAAAAAUUUAAAAUGUGGGUGUACCAUUAAGGUGUAAAACAAAAGUUUGACUUCUUGUUGGCAAGAGAUUAAAACGGAUUGGUUGAAAAUUUCCUUCAUGUUAAGUAAUUCUGAUCAUCUUAUAUGCCUACUCAUCCAUUCCACCCCUACAACACUGUCCAAAAUGGAAAGGCUUACCCUAAAAAUCCCAUAACUGUUAAAUUCAUAUACUCCUCACUGUUCCUGAGUAAAUUCUUUGUGUUCCAGUUUAUGUGUGUAUGUUAGAAAGCCCUAAUUCUUUCUGCAGACUCUUUACAUGGCCCAGGGGACAUAUUAUUCUUUACCCUUUUAGCACCAAUUUUUACAAACACAGCAUUUCUCUCAUUUAAAAAAAGCGUCUGACAAGCCGCUGAGUAGAAGCGACUGAACCUUUAGGAGUUUCAUAGUGCCUUCAACCAACAAUGAAAAUUCUGUUUUUCAAGGCGUUUCAAAUUCUUGAGCCAGUGUCAAAGACUCAUUUAGAAACAAUAUGACAUGUUCAGAGGAAAAGAAUUACAUCUAGUCUUGCCCAGAAAUCAUCCUUUUGCUCCCUCUUUUGUAAGAGCUAAUACUGCAGACCAGUCCCAUCUUAACUGCAUCAGAAAGAGGAGGCUCGUGGAAGGGAGGAAAUGUGGGCCGUUCUGUCUCCACGAGUGUCAUUGCUUGGCUUCCUUGGCUUCUCACGAAGCAUUUAAUUGGACUUAGUCACAUAUUUGUUCACUGACAUGGCAGCCUGCAAAGCACAAUGCCUCUCUGUUUUUCUCUGUUUGCUUUAAAAAAUUUUGUUUUUAAAAUUUGAGCUCUAAAGCAUGUUAGAGCUCCUCCUGCUGGAUUUAAAAAAAAAUAACUGGGACGAUUAAUAAAUGGUAAUUCUUUUUCUUCAUAUUUACCACCUGGGCUAAUAGAAGUGACAGAAGCCUAUCAUGUGGUGCACUUAAAACUGACCUUUUAAUUCAUCAGGUAUGAAGGUCAGGCAGAAAGAAAAUGUUGGUGCUACACAACUCAUCUCUCAGUCUUCAAAUUCCUCAUGCUCUUUUUUUUUGCUGUUGUUAAAAAAAAAAAAAGGAAAAGGAAAGGUUAUUUUUCUGUGAGUAUUUCUAGUUACAUAGUUACCCCAAGUCACAUCCCCAUGCUUGAAAGGUUCUUGCUCCCUCUCAGAAAGGGACAAAAAGUCUUUUCUAUCUUCCCAAAGCAGAAAUGAAUUGUGCAGUCAUACAGAGAUUCGAAGUGUUGCCUUUUUCCUCCCUAUCCUUUCUUCUUUUUCCUUCUUCCUCCUGAUUUCCUCCUCCUUCUCAGAAGCGGACACUUGCCUCGCCCAGUAGCUAGUUCUCAGCACCUCCUUUCUGCCUCCUCCUUCCCCUAAAUGGUGGCAGUUGGCCUCUCCCUCUCCUGGUGCCUGAAGUGGGAGUGACGAGAAGGGUCAGAAAAAGGUUUACCCCAUUCACCAUCAGUGGGAGUAGGUUUCUACAGCACAUAAGUUUCUGGAGGUCUCUUUAGGAAUAAGAGAGAAAGGAGGGGGGAUAGAAGGGAGAUAGGAAGAAAGGAGGGAAGGAGGGAAGGGGCAGGAAAGGAGGGAAGGAGGGAAGGGGCAGGACAGGAGAAAAGGAGGAAAGGAAGGAGCAAAGGAAAAAAAAUCACUUGUAAAUCUCUGUAAAACCACUUCCUUUCUCUGCAUGCUUUCUCACACUGUAUCCCUCUUGCCUUCUGCUUCUCUGCGUUUCUUUUAGCUCUUUCCUCCCCCAAGUUUAUAAUCUCAAUGAUAUAGUACAAAGGCCAAAAUACUUAAAAGUUAAUCUCGGAAAGUAAUGCUUUUUAGAAAUCAUAUUUUAAUACAACUAAAAAUCCUUCAUGUUACCUGUUUCAUGACUUUAUUAGGACUUGGGACAAAACAAGUCAUUUGGUAUUUGUGAUAAAGAAUAAGACAACCCUUGAUUUCUCAAACUUCAGUACUUUCUGGCUUUCUUUCCUUUGCACAUACCUUUCCUAUUCCUGGAAUGCUAGUCCCCUUAACUUUCCGUACUUUCUGGAAGUCCUUCCAACCUCCUAGCCUCCUUCCAACUCUAAGCUAGGACUCCAGAUGUUUCUGAAACUCCUGAAGCAAAAAUUUUAGCAUAAUCCUACUGUGGUCAUAGUUAACUUGUCUCUCUCCAUCUCAACAAGAAACUUCUUCAGGGCAGUGACUCUUUAUUUCUGUAUCUCUACCUCUUAACACAGUACCUAGUACAUAAGUAGGGCUUACUGAGGGGAUGAAGGAAUAUAAAAUGAAUUGACUUGCAAGCCUCAAUCAAAAUUUAUUUUGAAACUAGCCCGAUACUUAUUUUAAAAACCAACUUAAACACACUUUCUUGUUCUAUUCUAUUGAAAAGCUUGCCUGAGUGAAUGUUGUAAAAUUCUUUUUACAGAUCAUAAACUGAGGAGAGUUAAUGUGGGUAAAUCAUCCUUUAAGCUGCUUUUUUGCCACAACCACAGAAGUGGGUAUAUUAGGCACCAUGCCUAUGGGUGAAAUCCAAGUCAGAUAUGUAGGACAAUGUAAAGAAAGUGUGACAAAGCAGAUUAUAUUACCAUUUAUGUCACAGGCUAAUUUAUACAGGAUAUUACCUGUUUGUAUCAUCAAAAAAUUGUGAACUAUUUUUCUCCCUAUGUUCUGAUUUCAAAUUCCAUGAAUUGAUUCAUAUUUUCCCAAUGACAUACAUUAUAAAAUCAUGGGUUCAUUUUCACAGGGGAAAGAAAUGCUGGCUCUAAUACACUGCAAGAAUCAUAUUAGAGAAUUCCUUAAAUCCUUUAAGUGGGCUCCAAGUUCUGUGUUCUUUCCAGCAUCUACUGUAAACUAUUCUUGGAUAGUAUUGGCUCAUUCUGUUGCUACAGCCAAAAAUUCCAAAAAUAUGCUGAAUAGCACCCUAUAGUAUUUCUUACAGUAAAUUAUAAAAUAUUAUCUUCCAUGUGGACAAAAUCAUGACUGUUAUAGCAUUUUUCUGACUUUAAAUAAAUGCCCAAAAUAAGAAGUAGAGUGCAAAUACAUCGCUGAAAUUUAAAAUACAGUGUCCCAAAAUUUGUUCUCUUAGAGCAGACAUUCACAAGAAGAAGUAGGGGUCCUGCAUCACAGCUGCCUUCCAUUUUACCUAGAAGUGUGCUCCAACCCGAUUUAUCUUUGGGCCCAUUCACACUCAUUGAUCUACCGCUUGGGACACUGCCCUCAGCAGGUGCUGUGGAAAGCUGCAAGAGGCGUAGGAGUAAUCUUGGUUCAUAGAAGGUUUUGAAUGUUGUUCAGAUGAUAAGAUAUGCAUGCACGCCUCAAACUUCAAAAAAAAUGAUGCAAGCAUUAAAUGAUUCAAGAGGGUCAUUGAGAAGUAAAGCAUUUCAAUUCCUGAAAACAUAGAAAAUGGUUUUUGUAGAUAAAACCCUUCAUUUUUUAUCAUAAAUAAGUUUAAAAAGGGUGGGCAAGUUGAUAUCAGAUUCUAGUGGCCCUUGGAAACCUGGGAUGUAUAACUCUCUCAUGAUCCUAGAUGUAUGUAAACUAAAUUUUGAGACAGUUAUAUUUUAAACUUUCAAUUAUAAUUUACAAGUAAAUCUUGCAAUGUAAAAGAAGCUACUGCAUAUCCUUUUUAUGCAAAUAACUACCCUUUUAAGCAGAUAUCUUCUCUAAAAAUGUCAGUCUUUGUAUAUCUUUUUGAAGGCUUUCUUUUAAUUUGGGUCCACCUAACUACUUAUGCUGGACUUCAAUCCUACCCUCUCCAAAGAUUAGAAUUUGGAAUGCACAGAGAUGCUUACCUAUUUAUUUUCAUAAGCAAAUACAAGCUUCCCUAAGCAAGUAGUAGUUAUUCUUCUGAUAAUGACUAACAACAACGACAACAAACACUGUAGUCCAGUAUCUUGGUCUUUAUAACAUAAGGCUAAAACUGCUUUCACCCAUGCUUAAGUCUAAUUCCUAAAGGUAUCAAAGUGUUUCUACAAGCAUUUCUUCAUCCUUCUUAAGAUUUCCAGCACUUUCUCUUUUUGUUUUUACUUUAUCUGGCAAGUAAAUUGAAUUGCUAAUAAAGCAAAGUAAAAAUCUUUUUUUUACUGAACAGUGGUUUCAAAGCAUAGUCCCAGGACCAGCAGCAUCUGGGAACUUAUUAGAAAUAUCCCACCACAUUAGAAAUGUUGGGUGGCACCCAGCAACCUGUGUUUUAACAAGGCUUCCAGGGAACUCUGAUGCAAGGUCCAAUUUGAGAACCAUUGCCAAGAGCAUAUCAAUCUAACUGCCCAAUAGAAAAAAUUCUGCACUGAAAGUCAUGAGACCUUAGUGCAAGCACAGGAAAGGAAGAAGACUGAACUACAUAGGCCCAUUCUGGCUUAAAAAUUUACCAGUCAGAUAAUUCCUACUUCCCAUCCUAUGGAGAAAUAAGGGCAGGGACAGAAAGGCCAAUCCAUUUCACAAAUCAGUAUUAUGCUAGCUGGAAGCAAGAAGCUAGAGGAAAGGUGGUUUUCACACCCACCCCACAAACUGAUACACCAAAGCAGUUUGCCCUUAUUGAGGUCUCCCUUAACUCCUGUUAAAAUGGGCCUCAUAUCAUGAACACUCAGGACCAGCUAAUCCAAAGAAGAGCAGAUGAAAUUUUAGUUCUUCUGUUCUUAAAAGACAAUAAAAUAAGGCAAGAAAACAAUGAUGCAUUCUUCUCUCUUAUCGGUAAAGCCAGUUUCUCCCCCACAAUGCCACCCACCCUGCAUGAGCAUUUGACUUUCUUACAAAAUUUGUCAUUGUCCACAAUACUGCAAACAGUCCAUCCCUGCAGCUACAAAUACAACUUCAAGUAUUACUUCUUCCCCUUUGAUUUGAAAGAAGAAACAUGGCUCUUCUAUGUAACCAUAAACCGCCCACAUACAACACAGUGUUUCAAUAAACACUAAGUGAUACAAGAUGCUCCAUUUCAAUAUAAUGCCUUACUUAACGAAGCUCAUUACUAAACAAAGCAACUGAGGAAAAUUUGGUACAAAACAAUAACUUUGCUUUCCCCAAAACAAACUGUCUUGUGAGGUGAAUGCCUUUGGAAACUCUUUGAAUGGUUAGGAACUGGACCAAUGAAAUGAACUUUAACAGUAAACUUUAAAUGUUUUCUGGUGUUGAAGUUAGCAAACAUCUUUAGCAUUGCAUAUUAAGAAAAUUCACCCUAAAUUGCUUUCUAGUACAGUUGUAUAUACAGAUUUUUGUUGUUACUGUUUUAGAAAAAAUAAAUAAAAUGUUUAUUUCUUCUGCAAGGUUUAGUGAGGAGCUCUUUAGGAUUUUUAAUGACUAAGUACAUAUUUGGGUUCCUUUAACUGCAACUAGGCAUAUUUCCAAGAUAUCAUAGUUACUUUGAGAGAACAUGAACAUUUUAUCUUUUAUUAUUUUAAUUAUUAAUUCACCAUCUAGCUAUGCAGUGCCUAUUAAAUGCAUGUCCCUAGGGACAUCCUUAAAGAGCUCAUAAUGAAUAAGUUAUCCUGAUUGACUGAUUUAUUUGGAAAAAAAUACAAUACUAUGAACCACAGGCCAUGCUAAGUUAUGGGAUAUGGUAGUGAAUAAGACUAACAAUAGACCUGGCACAUAGCAGAACCAUAUGUUCUCCUCAUCUCCUGUCUUGACUUCUUUCUGCAAUUGCCUGCUACUAUUGUGCUCUUGUCCCAGCCACAUGGUCCAAGGAUUAAAGCAGAUAUUAAUGAGAAUUUACUGUGCCAUAAGAGUACUUAAGUCUUUCUAUUCUCUAUCCACACCAUUGAAUUUUUCCCUUCAAUCGCCAUCAUUUAAGUUCCAAUUUCACUCAUUAUAGACCUACAUUCCUACUUCCAAGUUUUAUAUGCAGCAGUUACAAUCAUGUUUGCCAUCACUUUGACCACAUUAUUGUAUUUUCAGACUUCCCAGAGUGUAUUCUCAGACUCCGAAUUACAAAAUUUUGCCCCACUUUUCCACUUAAAAUGAAGUACUAUAAUAAAGCUACUUUCAUAUUUGUUUUAUUCCACUCAUCUUCCAUUCUGAAUAGAUGCUGAGCUCUUUAAAGUCAUGUAGCAUGAAGCAGUCCACAUAUUAGAUGCUCAAUAAAUAAUCUAUGCAAUAUAUAACUGGAAGUCUUGACAUAGAUCAUCUAGUCUGAUUGUACAAUUUGGCAACUGGAGCUAGAAUCCACAUUUUCUAACUUCUGAUCCAGGACUCUUUCUAUGUAAACAUAGUAUCUCAAAUAUAAGCUUCUGAUAAAUGCCUUAAAAGUGUAGCAUCCUUGGCCUCGCUAGACCUACUCACCUUGAUCUAGCCUAAACUCUAGCCUGGCUAAAUAUCUUGUUUAGGCACUUUUCAGUCAUUUCUUCAUUUGUCCAUUAUUCAACAAAUACUUAACCACUGCUUUCUAAUCACAUUGUACCAAAUGCUGAAUACACAUAAUAAAUGCAAAAUAUGUGGUUUCUUUUCUCAAGGAAUUUUGAAUCUAUUUGGGGGACACUGGUAAUAAUCUAGUAAAUAAAUACAUAAUCACAAGUAGGGUUACGUGCUACGAGAGACACAAACAUGAAGUCAUAGGGGAAGGCAGAGGAAGUCAGGAAAACUAUGGGAUGGUCCAGAAGGACUGAGGAAUAACAGUUAAGCCAAGAACAAAAGGAUCAAGAGAAGUCAGUUUCAUUCCUUUCUCUCUUGGCUACAAGCCUUGAUCCAAGCUAUCACAUAUUCAUGAAACGAUUUCCAAUCCAUCAUGCCAUGCUGUAUCCUACUUCUCACUGAAUUUGUAGUCUAAAAUCAACUUUUUAUUUAAUGAAAUCACCUAAUUAAUUCCAUUAUCAAAACUUCUGGUAGAAUUUCCCUCCUUAAAGCUCAAAUUCUGGCCAGUUCUCUCCUCCCACCAGCCAACUGGUUAAUUGCUAAGAAUACAUUUCCAUAGGUUACAUGAUUAUUUGACAAACUCCCUGAGGGCAGGGGGCUUAUUAUUUGGUAUUUAUUCCAAAUAUCUACUAAAGAACUGAGCAGUUAGAUACUUUAGAGUCACCAAGGAUCUCAAUCCUACAUGUCACUUUAGCUACUUUUUUUUUUUUGCCAUGGCCAUGAUUUACUCACAAAUAUCCUUGUAUUUAUAAGACCAAUGAAUAUCACAAGCAUUCAUUAGUUAUUUCUUGAUUCUAGGAGGAACUUUCAUUCAUUCAGUUAUCAAACAUUCAGUGACUGAAUGACAAGCAGUGAGCUAGAUACCACAGUUACAUGAAGAUGAUUAAGAGACAGCUCAUUUCUCAUCAGUGAAGAUAACAUAUAAGCCUAAUUAGAGUUCAGUGUGAUGACUAAUAAUAGAGAUUUGUUGAGAUGCUAUACAAACAACUGUAUCAGGAGAGGGGAAGGCAGGUCAGGGAAGGCUUCACUGAAGUAAGUCUUAAAUGAUUAGUUAGUAGUCUCAGAAGAUGACCAAAAUGACAUUGAGAAUGUAAUUGCAUGUAACACCAUGCUAAACACUGUAUGAAACAAGUUAAGUGGGUGUGACCUGCGCCCUUCAGAAACUUCCUAUCAAAGAAGAAAAUUAUGCAGAUUCAAGAUUCAGGACAUAAGUUAAACAUAUAUGGCCAUUUUAAAUGAAAAUAAGGCUGGGUACCAUGGCUCACACCUGUAAUUCCAGUGCUUUGUACCUCCCCAAAGAAAGAUUUCCUUUGAAGCCUCUUACACAUUUUUCAAGUGCAUGAGGUAAAAGGAAUUCUACUAAUAUCUAUGAGUUUGUGCCUAAAUAGUUAAUAUUUUCACCAUUAAUCAACAAUAUCUCUCCUGCUUUGAUUUUUCCUUGAUCGUGUAAUUUAAUUUUAUAGUUCCAUGAUUUUUCAACAACUAUUUUUUUCAAAACUAUUUUUCAAAACUAUUUUUCAUAAUAGUUUUCUUAAAUUUUUCUAACUUCACUUCUUCAUACCUGAGAAAGGACAUUCAAUUUGAUCAAUAUAGAGUUUCUAAUACAGAAGAAAAAUUUAUGACUAUAAUUCCAGAAGGAGUCUUUCUGAAAAAAUCAGUUGCAGAGUUUUAUCAAAAAGAAACAUUUCAAUUUGUAGACUUUGUCAAAUUUGGGGGGGUAAAAAAAUGACUACCCAAGAUACCAUAUAUGAAGUCAAGUACACAAAUACACUAAAAAAACUUAUUAAUAUAUUUAGGAAAUAAAUGUAGAAGCUUGAGGAAUAAAUAAGUAAUAAAUAAUAUUACUUGGUAAUGUUGAGACUCUCAAAUACAGUAAUAUUUCAUUAUCUAAAGUACGUUUGCUUAGUAAACUCAGCUACCAGAAACAUCAUUACCAACUAGAAAGUGAGUAAUACUACUAAUACCAAUACUAAAGUCUUUAAGACCCAAAAUAGGAACUAGAGCUCCUGCAAUUUAAACAGGCACUCAACACUGAGCCUAUUUACACUUGCUACAGAGAACUCUAAAGACUUGCUUUUCUGAUUUUUAGUGCUCUGUAAAUUACAAGCAUAAUAUAGAACAAAUUGGAGAAAGUCAAAAAGGCAAUGAGAAGUGAUAAUAAUAUCCUGAAAGAAAAAGGAAAAUUAUAUGUGAGAAAUAAAAAUUCAAAAGCCAUCAUUGUCUGAAACAGUAUACCUUAUUAGUUCCUGAGUUCAUUCUAUGUAAUUAUUAUAUUCUAUUGGCUAAGAUAUGUGCAGUACGUUUCAGAUGGCUUUCAAAUAGUUUCAUAUUUCUUAUUAGUAUUGGAAGGAAUGACUUCAGUUUUGAGAAAGAUUUGCAUAUGAAAAAAGACGUAAUUUUCAUUAAAACUACUAGAUAAAUGAAAGGUGACAAUGUUAAAAUCAUUACAGAUCAUAACCACUUCUGCUGGCCUGUAUGUGCAUGAGCAUGUGUGUAAUGGCUCUUUCUCAGUGUCCUUGGAACAAUGUUCUGCUAGAUAUUCUACUUGUUUCUUUACCUUUCUCUUUUUCUCUUUCUAGCCGGAGACCACCCCCAUCACCAACUCGUCCCACUAUAAUCCGCCCACUAGAAUCCUCCCUGUUAGACUAAACGAAGUGUCUGGCAUGGCAAUUAAUCACUAAUGAAUUAUGCGAAAGCAACAUAUUUGAUAACCGUUGCAGUAAAUCAUGAGUAGUCGCAUGUGUGGACAUCAGUAGGCAAGUAACCAGUUUUACUAAUGCAUUCAUCGCUCAUCUUCAUUGCUCAUGGUAUGUCAAACCUUUGGGGUUUGACUCAGAAACUGCUAACCUUUUAGAGGCUUUAUAUGUUGUACUGACCAAGGUAGGUUUGUAUAGCAGCCCUAUACUUUGGGGAUCAUUUGCCUACCAUGGCAUAUAUUUGAAAUUGCUUUGGACAAGUUUUCUAGGCUAUCUACCAGGUAGCUCAUUAAACGUAAUUCUUCAGAUAUGAGAUAGUGGGCUUAGACCUAAGCCAUACAUAUUUCUUUUCCCACAUUCUGUUUAGGAUGACAGUAAUUCUGUUGUCUACCAUUAAUGCUACUACCUACUCCAUAAUUGCCUAUUUAGCUCCUCUUUUCUUCCUUUUUAUUUCAUAAGACUGCUAGGAAGUGAUUUUUUAAAAUUAGGACUCCUUAAGAAUAAACUUUUCCAGAAGCACGAGGUAGUUUGCAAAGGAAAAGUCUGCACUGUUUGCUCUAAAGAGCUUCUCCUCAUUCCAAUGUGUUUUGCUUCAUGCUAGAAGCAUAUGCAACAGUGAAUAAAAGCUUCUUUUUUUGUUAAUCAGUCAAUAAAUUUGGCUAAUUAGUUUCAGAGUUCAAGGAAGAAGCAAAAUAUCACAUCUCUAGAAGUGUUGGGAAAAAUAUAAUUUCUUUCUUUACUUAUAUUCACCUCAUGGUAGGUUAUAUUGAAGGCUGACAUGGAGAAUGUUUACUUUUCUAUUUGGCAUAGCUAACUACACUUUGAUACUAACUCCAGUUUUACUAUUAUUAUUUUGGUUGGAAAAAAAAUUCACUCUUUACGUGCUAAUUUGUAAUCUUGUUUUGUAAGAAUUUAUCCUACCCUUGAAACAGGCUCAGUGUAACUGUAUAUCCAUUCUAGGCUUUCUUAAUAAAUCUUGAGGCUAUGGGAUAAUCACAUUUAAAGAAUGGUUCCUGAAAUGAAGUCAGUAGAAAUGGCAUGGGAUAAGAGCAGAGCUCACACUUUUACAGUUGCAGUAUUUCAAAGUCCCUAUCCAGGUCACUCCAGAAAAGGGUAUUGAAACGUUGAAAUCUAAAGCAAAUUUGCAAUUUCUUAAGAUUUCUAAAAUUUACCAGAACAGUUUAGCCUGGGGGUUAAUAGUUAAGUCUUGAGGCUAAGUUUUGGACUACCAAGGACCAGAUGAUUCACAUGUAGGAAACAGCCAGAAGCCAACUGGAAUUUUGUGUGCUAACUGUUCCCAGACAGCAGAGCAAGUAUUCACUGAGUAGGGGUGUCCCAUGACACUAUUUCAUAUUCUACAGAAGUAAAUCAGGUUUCACCAACUGAAAUGUCUCCCUUUGAAAGUAGCAAACAUGAUUUGUAUGUUAACUUAACUUUAAUUUCCUGUGUAGUUUACACCCAGAGCAGAUACUCAUAAAGUAUAAAGUAAAAACUUUUAACCAUUAUUAAACAGAGAACUUGCCAUGUUGAGUGCCAUUGUAUUGAACUUAUUCUAAAGGCUUAUGCUAACCCAUUUAUAAUUGGUAAAAAUCAGAAAAUACAAGAUUUACAUAAAGGUCAUUUCAACUUUUAAGGUUACCAGUGAUUGUAUAAAAACAUCACAAUCCUAAAUCCUCUCGUAUCUCACCCCAAACCCCAAACUGGGGGAAAAAAAGUUAACUCUUUGUGAAUGGAACCAAUGUGCAAGAUACAUACUGCAUUUUUAAAAUAGUGUCUCAGCUAAAUGGAAAACUGUUAAGCAAACAUCCAUAGUAAAACAAAUAAUCUUCAGUGAGAUCUUUUUAUAAAACUUCUUGUUUUUAGGAUUCCCUUUGCUUCUUCCUUUGAAUUCUCUAAAAUAGGCAGCUAACGGAUUAUAUACUUCAGGGUUUGGCUUUGUGCUAAAUGUGGUUUUGUGUUUUGCUGUAUUUCAAAAUUUUCCUUCUGUUAAAGGAAAAUAUUGUGAAUAACCACUGGUGUGUUCUUAGAUCAGCACAAACCAUGUCAAAAAAAAUUGGAGAUUUUUUUCCAAUUUUCCUUCCACUGAUCUUAGGCAGUAAUAAACAAUGGCAUUUGUCAUCUUUGGCACUUGCUUUUAGAUUAUAGUCCCACAGUUGCACUGCCCCAAUUGUCUACCUUUGUGGGUACAUUUUUGUUCUUUACUCCUAAGUUAUUUCUCAUAGAACCCAGCCUACUCUAGAAUUUCAGCAGUGACAUUGGAGAAUAUUUUUAAUUUGCUGCAGUACUAUGUCAUAUUAUUAGUAUGAAUCUCAUUUCCCAAAGGGUUUGUAUUCUGCUAAAAGGAGAUGCCAAUGUUGAAUGAAGUCUGAAACUCUAGUAUGUGCAUAGUUUGACGUGCAGCAUGCACACCAGGCCUUAAGAUGGGAAUGUAGCUUAAUGAUUUUCUGUUUCCCAUACCAUUUCUAAUCUUUUGUGUAAUUUUCUCUUAACUGAUUGCUCUGAUAUUGUAAACACAAUAGAUGUAGCUCUAUCAUGUCUAGCAUAAUUUAAAAAAUCAGUGUUUUUAGGAUUUGGGAAAAUAAACUGUAAAUGUUUAUUUGAUAGGUAAAUAUAGUUUUAUUGUCACAUGCUAAAUAUUGCAUGCAUAUUGACUAAUUGGAAUAACCAUUUACUCAAUUAUGGACAGCUUAUUGAAAUAGUAUUGAUUUAGAAAAAGUAUAUUGCAUUUCUAAAAAACAUCUACCAAGGUUACUCGUCUGAAUAUUGCUUUUAGCCGUGUUUUAUAACAUAGACGAGCAGUAGGGUCUGUUUAUUAGCAAAUUUCCUAUUUGUUCCAAUACAAACUCACUUUAUUCUAAAGUAUAUUAAUGAAACCAGUUCCUGUGAUGUAACUGUAAGCCUUCUCGACUUAGACUUAAAAAGUGGUCACAUAGAUUAAUUUUGUGACUUUUUAGUAUAGACUGUAGCCAUAAUUCUCAAAUAUGAAAUGGGACCUAAUACCAGUAUGUGAUAAAUGUUGAUGUUUUCUGUGUACAAACACAUUUUCUAUGCAUGUGUCUCUGUGUAUAUGGCAUAUACCUAGUAAGUAUGUUUCUGUAAGUAUGUGUAUUUUAUGUCCAUUUGAGUAGGUAGGUAGGUUUUAAAAAUACUAGUUAAAAUGCCACAAGCAUGAGUGUGAUUGUAUGUGCACUGUGUGUAUAUAUAUAAAUAUAUGUAUAUGUAUGGUUGUAAAUAUCUAUGUAUACAUGUACUUAGUAUGUGUGGUAUCAGGAUAUUUUUUAAACUGUGAUAAUACAACAGAUAGCUUUGAAUGAUCUGCCAUAACAUGUGGUAACAAUAGUUCAUUUCUCAUAACAUAUAUGAGGUAUACAAAAUUUUCUAACUCCAGAUUGUAGUCAUUUUGAGAGGUACAAAGCUCAUAAUUACCAUGACAACAUGGUAAUGUCCAUAGACAUUUGUAUCUGAAUCCACAAGAAGAUCUGAAUCUAAGAAGGAAUUACCUUUGACAAUAUUUUUCGGUAAGAAGUAAAACCUCUGGAGACCUAUCUUUAAGAUCUCUAAUUGGAAUUAUAAAUUAUUUUUGGAUUGCUGAGCUGAAUCUUAAAAAGCCAAGUUGAUAUACAUAGUCAUUUUUCCUCUAUGGUAGAAGUAAAAAAAAAAAAAAAGGACAUAGCAACAUUAAAGUAGUGGAUUUUUCUGAGUAAAUUUGCUGAAAAUAUAAGAGAGAAGCUAUCUAAUACCUUGGAGGUAGGUCAUCCACUUUUUCAGGUAAACAUUUUUCAUUUGGCAAAUGGCAUAAUUAUUUGAAAGUGACAGGAAUCUCCUCAGAAUGAAGAAUAAAGCCUACUAGGUCUCUAACUGUUGAACUCAUGAAAGAAGAUAGUGUAUGAGACUUAAGCCAUGAGUUUUGUAUCAUUUCAAUUAGAAGACUACUAGCUGUGAGCUCAGAGUUUAAUGUAAAUGAAUCUAGAUGAUUUUGAAGAAAUGAUUAUUCGUUCACCAGAUCACUCAUUGUACAUUCUAAAAAGCUCAAAUGAGUCUUCUAGAUACUCUUACUCAUCCUGUCUGGUUGCUAUGUUUAAAAUUAUGUGGUGCUGUGUAGGUGAAACUUUAAGAAUAUUUUUGAAGCAUAUGUAAUAUAUGCACUGCUAUUUGUGUGUGUGUGUGUGUCUUUGUAUAUAUGUAAGAAUGUGUGUAUGUGUGAGAGCAAGAGAGAGGAAACUCAAAGAGGAGUGUUUGUCUUAAGACCUGUUCAUACUGGUAUAUUGGUGAGACUUCUCACUUCUGGUUGGAGGUUUCACAUAUGGCUCAACUCAAGUCAUUAAUCUCUUUUUAAUUUUUACUCUUGAAUUCCUUAAACUUCGCUCAUUAUGAAAUGUUUUAAAAUUAUGACAAAAAUUACUCUGUCUAACCACUUGCCUUGUCUGCUACCAGUUUGUUAAAAAUUAUUCCCCCCAACCAGUAAUUCCACCAGUACUACUUGAUUUGUGUUAUAUUUCCUAUGUACAUGUACAGCCUUUGUUUUGCUUGCUUGUCUAUUUUUACUUUCCCUUUUUUGGGUCAAAUUUUUCUUUUGCUUUGUUUGAAGAAGGAAUAUACAGAAGUAAAAUCUUGUCUUCUCUGCUGAUUCUUUAAUUAAUAUGAGCCGGAUACUUUCCACUGUCUUCUUGGCACUUUCAGGAUUUCUUAAUGCUGAUAUAUGGACUCUUAGAAUGGAAUUUUUGAAGAAAAAUCUCAAAGCCUGUAUCGUUCUUGAAGGUCACAUGUACCUAUUGUGAAAAUGUGAAGCUGUAUUUCUGAAGCUGAAAUAAAUUAUAACAUUUGAAGGA